GCUUCCGGCACCGGCCGAGGUGCGGGUCGCCUCCAGAGGUGCGUGGUCGUGGCGCGAGGGAUCCUGAGGCUGCUCCAGCAGUGCGCCGCCGCCGUCUCCUGGGGCGGCUUGGGUUAGCCGGGAGGUGGGUCAGAGGCUCGCCCCGUGCCCUGCGUCCGGGCGUCUCCUUAGGGCGCGUCUUCGGGUCCGGCCAGCGGUGCUGAAAAAGGGAGAAGGUUGGGGGUAGGGAGGAAACAAGAUCCCAGUUCAAUAGAUUUCUCCGCAGAUCCUGUGCCUUCAAACCCUACGAGUCCAUACUUUAAAACAAAAUGAAGAAAGUAAGGCUUAAGGAACUAGAGAGUCGCCUGCAACAAGUGGAUGGAUUUGAAAAGCCCAAGCUACUUCUGGAACAGUAUCCUACCAGGCCGCACAUUGCAGCAUGUAUGCUCUAUACAAUCCAUAACACUUAUGAUGACAUUGAAAAUAAAGUCGUUGCAGAUCUAGGAUGUGGUUGUGGAGUACUUAGCAUCGGAACUGCAAUGUUAGGAGCAGGGUUGUGUGUUGGAUUUGACAUAGAUGAAGACGCAUUGGAAAUAUUUAAUAGGAAUGCAGAAGAGUUUGAGUUAACAAAUAUUGACAUGGUUCAAUGUGAUGUGUGCUUAUUAUCUAACAGAAUGUCCAAGUCAUUCGAUACAGUAAUUAUGAAUCCUCCCUUUGGGACCAAAAAUAAUAAAGGGACAGAUAUGGCUUUUCUAAAGACUGCUUUGGAAAUGGCAAGAACAGCAGUAUAUUCCUUACACAAAUCCUCAACUAGAGAACAUGUUCAAAAGAAAGCUGCAGAAUGGAAAAUCAAGAUAGAUAUUAUAGCAGAACUUCGAUAUGACCUGCCAGCAUCAUACAAGUUUCACAAAAAGAAAUCAGUGGACAUUGAAGUGGACCUAAUUCGGUUUUCCUUUUAAAAGCCCCGCAAACAAAAGUCGUUUAAAACCUAUUUAAAAUGAAUAAAAAAUUGGUUUACUAAA